GUAGCGUGAUGACGUAAGCGGCGUUGGCGUGGUGUGGUAGGAGUGGUUGCGCGUGUUGCGGCCCGGGUUCUGUUCGUAGGUUUACAAUUGUCGCGGGUAGUGGGGCGCCCCAGCUGCCAACUGCACGUGGUUUCUUUCUGGCGUUUGCCUAGUGUCCUGUCCAUUCCGCCCCGUUGGGAAGUGGGAAGCGGAGAGGUUCUGUGGGGACAGAGCUGGGAGUCCUGAAGGAGAAAGCGCGCAGCCGAGGGGCUCUGGAGUGCCUUAGAGCAGAGCUGCGGCCGCGGAAGGGGAGCAGCUGAGAAAGGAGGGCCGCUGCAGGCGGGGUUCGAACCGUGGGGUCUGGGCUGCUCCCGCGGAGGGCCUGGGCGGACGCGGGAUGCUGGGGGUCCGCUGCCUGCUGCGGUCCGUGCGCUUCUGUUCCUCCGCCCCCUUCCCCAAGCACAAACCUUCAGCCAAACUGAGCGUGCGGGACGCUCUCGGGGCUCAGAACGCGAGUGGGGAGCGCAUUAAGAUCCAGGGAUGGAUUCGUUCUGUCCGAUCCCAGAAGGAAGUCUUGUUCCUGCAUGUAAAUGAUGGGUCAUCUUUGGAAAGCCUUCAGGUUGUUGCAGAUUCAGGCCUUGACAGUAGAGAAUUAAAUUUUGGGAGUUCUGUGGAAGUACAAGGGCAGCUGAUAAAAAGUCCAUCCAAAAGGCAAAAUGUGGAACUGAAGGCAGAAAAAAUUAAAGUUAUUGGAAAUUGUGAUGCCAAGGAUUUCCCCAUCAAAUAUAAAGAGAGGCAUCCUCUGGAGUAUCUGCGACAAUAUCCUCACUUUAGGUGUAGGACUAACGUUCUGGGUUCUAUAUUGAGGAUUCGCAGUGAAGCGACAGCUGCUAUUCAUUCUUUCUUUAAGGACAGUGGCUUUGUACAUAUUCAUACUCCAAUAAUCACAUCCAAUGACUCUGAGGGAGCUGGAGAACUUUUUCAACUUGAACCUUCAGGCAAACUUAAGGUACCUGAGGAGAAUUUCUUCAAUGUUCCUGCUUUCUUAACUGUCUCAGGACAACUUCAUCUAGAAGUGAUGUCAGGAGCUUUUACUCAAGUGUUUACCUUUGGUCCGACCUUCCGAGCUGAAAAUUCUCAGAGCCGGAGGCACCUGGCAGAGUUUUAUAUGAUAGAAGCAGAGAUUUCUUUUGUUGACAGCCUUCAAGAUCUUAUGCAGGUUAUAGAGGAACUGUUCAAGGCUACAACAAUGAUGGUUCUCUCAAAAUGUCCUGAAGAUGUUGAACUCUGUCACAAAUUCAUAGCACCUGGCCAAAAGGACAGAUUAGAACAUAUGCUAAAAAACAACUUUUUAAUCAUUUCUUAUACUGAAGCAGUGGAGAUCUUAAAGCAAGCAUCCCAGAACUUCACCUUUACCCCAGAGUGGGGUGCUGACCUACGGACUGAACAUGAAAAGUACCUGGUGAAGCACUGUGGCAACAUACCUGUCUUCGUUAUUAAUUAUCCAUUAACACUCAAGCCUUUCUACAUGAGGGAUAAUGAAGAUGGCCCUCAGCACACGGGCUGUAAUAACUGGCUGUAAGUUCGCAAGAGUUCCUGUAAUGGAUGCAGUGCAGUCUUGAAAAAAAUAAGACAGGUGUGUUUCAUAGGUGCCUUCUUUAGGGAACCAAAAGAGAAGGAUGGGGAAAUAUCUAAUCUACACUUGUAACUUUUGGCCAGAGGGUAAUAAAUAGUAAAAUGGUAUGUUUUUACAGUUAUAAUUUAUCUUCCUUUCUCCCCACCUCUCAGUAGAAAUGAAGGUAUGCGCUGUGGUGUACUGAAAAGUACACAGGAUGCAGAGUGGUUCUGGGUUUGAAAUCUAGAUACCUUACUAGUUACCUGUGUCACCUCAGGCAAGUCUCUGUGAUCUUUCAGCCUCAAUUUCUCCCUCUGUAUAAUCAGAGAAUUGGAUUAAGUGACCUCUAAAGUAUUACCUCUCUAAGAUUCUCUGAUUUCCUGUAGCCUAAGUUUUUCUUCAUAUGCAUGGAUAAGACUAACUUAUAAAUUACUGAGCAUAUUUGAUCAUUUGAAAGGGACAGAUCAUGGGAAAAUGAAUCUAAGCAAAUAUGCAAAAUGCCAUAUGCCUCUGAGGCUGGUCUCCAGGUAAGUCCCUCAAAGCCAGGUGGCAGAUGUUCAGCUGGGGGAGUGGCUUCACAGAGAAGAAUAGUCUUUUAUUCUACACACGUGUAAUUAGGAAAAAGUGACUGCCCCUCAGUCCUUGAUGAGAUGCCACAAUCACCAGGUAGUGUUCUAAUUUUCAAAAUUAUAUCAGUAUUACUUAGCAAACCAGAGAAAGGUCAGCAUUAGUGGGCAUUCAGUAAAGUACAUACUGUGAAGUCAACUCAGAAAGGAGAAUACUCAGCCAAGGGGUGUGCAAUAAAUUUCCCAGAGCUGUGGCUAAUUAACCAACCUGCAUCAAAAUAGCUCGAGCCACCAACCAACAGAAAUAGUGAUGAAGGGAAUUGCCAAUUUUCCCCAUAUCUAGGACUAAAGAGAAUCCUAGAAAUUUUUGUCAAAAUUGAAAGUAUCCAUUUCAGUCUGUCGUAAAAUACUUUGAGAUUCUUUAUCAUGACAUAUUUUAUAUUAAUACUUUGAAUUGUAGAGUUAGGGAACAUAGGGAAGAGAAAUCCUUUUAUGUGUGUGAUACAGACUUCUAAGGUUUUGUUACCAAACUGUUUCUCCCAUUUCAGUCUUCCCAGUGUGUCUUAAUUGAACAAGUUUGGUUAAAGCAACUGAGAUAAAAGUGAACGUAAAUGCCUCCUAAGUCUUUUGGUAGAGUAAGAGUGUCGAGGAAUCUUCAUUAUUAAAAGUAGCAAGGAAAAGACAUUUAGGGAGUUGAGAAAUUAUUUAUAUUGUCUCACUUAACUAAAUAAGAUUAACUUUGUAAGAUUAGAGAUUACUUAAAACAUGGUAGACAGAGGAAAAUGGAAGAAAAGAUUAACAAAGAUUAAAUUUUUGACGUUCCAAAUUGACAUCUAUUAUUGAGUACCCGUGUGGCAAGCAUAACGUUAAAACAUUCAAAAGAGAAAACAAUAAUGUUUAUCGAGUAUGUGCCGAUAAUUAACUUUUAUCCCUUUCUUACAGAUGAGGCUGCUACCUCUCAGUGCAGCAGUAUAGUCACUCAUGCAAAAUCACACCGCUAGCAGGUAUUGAAGCUAGGCUGUAAAGGCAGAAAUACAGCAUAUAUGGCAGCUUCAUUAGAAUCCUGAUCUUUCUGGGAGUGAAGAGUUUGUGUGGGGUGGCAGGAAGAGCUAUGGACUUAGAGCCAGGAGACUUGGGUUUUGUUCCUGGAUAUACCACUUGAUCUUUCUUGUCCUCAGUAUUCUCAGGGGAUCAUAGUCAAUCUCUGGUGAUAGAGGUCAGGAAAGAGGUUACUUUUGGUAGGGGUAGUAACUAAAAGAAGACCUUAGGAGGACUUUUUUGGGGUACUGCUAUUGUUCAGUUUAUUGAUCCGUAUGGUGCUUCAUGGUGUGUUUGUGAAAAUUUAUAGAACUGUAUACUAGUUAUUUGUGUACUUUUUACACAUAUUUUAUACUUUAAGUUUACUUUAAAAGGGAAUUACACACUUGUAUCAUCACAGGUUUGUUGUGGAAAUCAGAUGAACAAAUGUUUUUAAAAUUGCUUUAAAAAUUAAAAUUCUAUGCUAUAAAAAUAAUGGAGUAAGGAAUUAUUGGGUGAUAAAGAUGGCUAGACAAGAUAGGAACAAUUAUGGAGAGAUUGGAGUGUUACAGAUAGCUUGGGCUUUAUCCAGUAAAAAACAGAGAGGCAUUGUAUGUAUUCUAAGAUACUGGCAAGAUGAAAAAAUUAACCUGACAUAUAGAAUGGAUUGGGGAAGGGGGGAAUUAAAGACACAUAAGAUAAUUAUGGGACUUUUGCUUAUAAUCUCAACAGUGAAAAUGGAGAGAAAGAAAUGAACCUAAAACAUUCUGAAGGAAUAAACAGUGGUCUGUGUGUUAGUCCAUUUUACUGAAAUAGAGUUGCUCUAAGUUGCUAUAAAAAAAUACCUGAGACUGGCUGGGCACGGUGGCUCAUGCUUGUGAUCCCAGCACUUUGGGAGGCCAAGGCAGGCAAAUCACAAGGUCAGGAGUUCGAGACCAGCCUGGCCAACAUGGUGAAACCUGUCUCUACUAAAAAUACGAAAAAUUAGCUGAGCGUAGUGGCAGGUGCCUAUAAUCCCAGCUACUUGGGAGGCUGAGGCAAGAGAAUCGCUUGAACCCGGGAGGUGGAGGUUGCAGUGAGCCGAGAUCACGCCACUGCACUCCAGCCCAGGCGACAGAAUGAGGCUACAUUAAAAAAAAAAAAAACACCUGAGACUUGGUAAUUUAUAAAACAAAGAGUUUUAUUUGGCUCGUGGUUCUGCAGACUGUACAAGAAUGGCAUCAACUUCUCAGCUUCUGGUGUGGCCUCAGGAAGCUUUUACUCAUGACAAAAAGGCAAAGAGGGAACAGGCAUGUCACACAGCAAAACAGAGAGCAAGAAAGAAGGGAAGCGAUGUCAGUCUGUUUUAAACAACCAGUUCUCAUGUGAACUAAUAGAGCAAGAAGCCAUUACCAUCGGAAUGGCACAACGCCAUUCAUGAGGAGGCCACCCCCAUGAUCCAACACCUGCCCCUAGGCCCCACCUCCAAUAUUAGAGGGUCACAUUUCAACGUGAAUUUGGGAGGGCACAAAUAUCCAAACCAUAUCAGUCUAUGAAAUAAACUAGAAAGAAAAGAUAAGGAAGAGAGAAGAGUCACAAGUCAUUCCCAUAGGUCAUACUUUAAUUAUAAAAAGUAGAGUGGUGCCGUUUACUGAAAUGUUGUCCUCUCUCAAGUGGAGGAACUCAUAAGUGAACCUUUGUGGAGUUCUCAACUGAUGUUUUCUUCUGGUUCACUUGAAAUUUAGAGCUCACUAAGGAAGGAAGCAAUGUGGUAAAACAGUCUUGACCAUGAGGGAAAGGGAAUACAUGUUUGGGAGCAAGGUUGCUGCUGUUGAUCUUCUGGUUCCUGGAGUUGGGGAACUCUUUGGAGGAGGCCUCAGAGAAGAACGAUACCAUUUCUUAGAGGAG